AAGGGCCGCAGAGCCUGGCGCGGAGCCGGCGAGAUUUUGGUGGGGUCUCACCUGUUGCGUGACUCCCCCACAGUCCGGCCGCGGGAGUCCGACCCUGAAUGCCCAGGGAGUGUUGAGAGAAAUCUGGACGAGUUUCGGGUCCCGCUCCCUUGGGAGCACGUGGCCUACCAGCCUCUCGAUUGCAGGGUUGGGUGGUCGCGACACCGGGGUCGCCUUGAGGCCAGUCCGGCUGCCGAGGUCUGCGGGAGUCCACCUCCGGCCAGCUGGCAAUUUUGAAAGACUGCCUUACUUUCCCCAUCUCAGUGCCAGGGCAGGGGCCCUUGGAGUGACUUGGCUGGGGUCUGUGGCCCGAUCCCCCUGCCGUCCCUCAGGACCCGGGCUUUCUGCUGUACAGACUUCUCGUGGGCAGCCUCCCCUCGGAACUCGGGCAUCAUGGCCUCAGGCCCAGCCACCAUCAGUCACGUCACUCCUGGGACUGAGGAGGCAGGGGAGGGAUAAGGGGCAGAGAUGGAGGCCCCACUCCCCGAGGUUGCCUAGACAACAUGAGAAAUCGUGGCCAGGGCCUCUUCCGCCUGCGGAGCCGCUGCUUCCUGCAUCAGUCACUCCCGCUGGGGGCGGGGCGGAGGAAGGGGUUGGAUGUGGCAGAGCCAGGCCCCAGCCGGUGCCGCUCAGACUCCCCCGCUGUCGCCGCCGUGGUCCCAGCCAUGGCAUCCUAUCCAUCUGGCUCUGGCAAGCCCAAGGCCAAAUAUCCCUUUAAGAAGCGGGCCAGCCUGCAGGCCUCCACUGCAGCUCCAGAGGCUCGGGGUGGUCUGGGGGCCCCUCCGCUGCAGUCUGCCCGAUCCCUGCCGGGCCCCGCCCCCUGCCUCAAGCACUUCCCGCUCGACCUGCGCACGUCUAUGGAUGGCAAAUGCAAGGAGAUCGCCGAGGAGCUGUUCACCCGCUCACUGGCUGAGAGCGAGCUCCGUAGUGCCCCGUAUGAGUUCCCCGAGGAGAGCCCCAUUGAACAGCUGGAGGAGCGGCGGCAGCGGCUGGAGCGGCAGAUCAGCCAGGAUGUCAAGCUGGAGCCAGACAUCCUGCUUCGGGCCAAGCAAGAUUUCCUGAAGACGGACAGUGACUCGGACCUACAGCUCUACAAGGAACAGGGUGAGGGGCAGGGUGACCGGAGCCUGCGGGAGCGUGAUGUGCUGGAACGGGAGUUUCAGCGGGUCACCAUCUCUGGGGAGGAGAAGUGUGGGGUGCCGUUCACAGACCUGCUGGAUGCAGCCAAGAGUGUGGUGCGGGCGCUCUUCAUCCGGGAGAAGUACAUGGCCCUGUCCCUGCAGAGCUUCUGCCCCACCACCCGCCGCUACCUGCAGCAGCUGGCUGAAAAGCCUCUGGAGACCCGGACCUAUGAACAGGGCCCCGACACCCCUGUGUCUGCUGAUGCCCCGGUGCACCCCCCUGCGCUGGAGCAGCACCCGUAUGAGCACUGUGAGCCAAGCACCAUGCCUGGGGACCUGGGCUUGGGUCUGCGCAUGGUGCGGGGUGUGGUGCACGUCUACACCCGCAGGGAACCCGACGAGCAUUGCUCAGAGGUGGAGCUGCCAUACCCUGACCUGCAGGAAUUUGUGGCUGACGUCAAUGUGCUGAUGGCCCUGAUUAUCAAUGGCCCCAUAAAGUCAUUCUGCUACCGCCGGCUGCAGUACCUGAGCUCCAAGUUCCAGAUGCAUGUGCUACUCAAUGAGAUGAAGGAGCUGGCCGCCCAGAAGAAAGUGCCACACCGAGAUUUCUACAACAUCCGCAAGGUGGACACCCACAUCCAUGCCUCGUCCUGCAUGAACCAGAAGCAUCUGCUGCGCUUCAUCAAGCGGGCAAUGAAGCGGCACCUGGAGGAGAUCGUGCACGUGGAGCAGGGCCGUGAACAGACGCUGCGGGAGGUCUUUGAGAGCAUGAAUCUCACGGCCUACGACCUGAGUGUGGACACGCUGGAUGUGCAUGCGGACAGGAACACUUUCCAUCGCUUUGACAAGUUUAAUGCCAAAUACAACCCUAUUGGGGAGUCCGUCCUCCGAGAGAUCUUCAUCAAGACGGACAACAGGGUAUCUGGGAAGUACUUUGCUCACAUCAUCAAGGAGGUGAUGUCAGACCUGGAGGAGAGCAAAUACCAGAAUGCAGAGCUGCGGCUCUCCAUUUACGGGCGCUCGAGGGAUGAGUGGGACAAGCUGGCGCGCUGGGCCGUCAUGCACCGCGUGCACUCCCCCAACGUGCGCUGGCUGGUGCAGGUGCCCCGCCUCUUUGAUGUGUACCGUACCAAGGGCCAGCUGGCCAACUUCCAGGAGAUGCUGGAGAACAUCUUCCUGCCACUGUUCGAGGCCACUGUGCACCCUGCCAGCCACCCGGAACUGCAUCUCUUCUUAGAGCACGUGGAUGGUUUUGACAGCGUGGAUGAUGAGUCCAAGCCUGAAAACCAUGUCUUCAACCUGGAGAGCCCCCUGCCUGAGGCGUGGGUGGAGGAGGACAACCCACCCUAUGCCUACUACCUGUACUACACCUUUGCCAACAUGGCCAUGUUGAACCACCUGCGCAGGCAGAGGGGCUUCCACACGUUUGUGCUGAGGCCACACUGUGGGGAGGCUGGGCCCAUCCACCACCUGGUGUCAGCCUUCAUGCUGGCUGAGAACAUUUCCCACGGGCUCCUUCUGCGCAAGGCCCCCGUCCUGCAGUACCUGUACUACCUGGCCCAGAUCGGCAUCGCCAUGUCUCCGCUCAGCAACAACAGCCUCUUCCUCAGCUAUCACCGGAAUCCGCUACCGGAGUACCUGUCCCGCGGCCUCAUGGUCUCCCUGUCCACUGAUGAUCCCUUGCAGUUCCACUUCACCAAGGAGCCGCUGAUGGAGGAGUACAGCAUCGCCACCCAGGUGUGGAAGCUCAGCUCCUGCGAUAUGUGUGAGCUGGCCCGCAACAGCGUGCUCAUGAGCGGCUUCUCGCACAAGGUAAAGAGCCACUGGCUGGGACCCAACUAUACCAAGGAAGGCCCUGAGGGGAAUGACAUCCGCCGGACCAAUGUGCCAGACAUCCGCGUGGGCUACCGCUACGAGACCCUGUGCCAGGAGCUGGCGCUCAUCACGCAGGCAGUCCAGAGUGAGAUGCUGGAGACCAUUCCAGAGGAGGCGGGUAUCACCAUGAGCCCAGGGCCUCAAUGAGCCUGGUCCAUGAAGUGCCCACCACAUCGCAGCACUUUUACCACGUUUUGUCCUCAGACCCCGCCCAUGCUGUGUGGUCUCUGCAUGUCUCCAUUCUUCUCUGUCUCUGUCUUGCAUGUCUCCUACCAUGUCACUGUCCCUGGGCCACCCAGUGAAAGCAAAGCCUGGGAAUCUGCUCAUUGUUGUUUGGGCUCAGGUAUUGAGCCUGAUGGCCCAGGUAUUGAGGGCCUCCCCUGCUGGUGGCCCUGUCCUGGGAUCCUCAGAAGCCUGACUGUCCUAUGGGCUUCUCCAGUGUCCACAGGGGCUUGGGAUGGUUGUGGGGGGCUGGCCCCUCUAGCCUUUCCGGUCCUUCCUGGGCAAAUCUAAGCCUUGGCCAGGGCCGAAGUUUAGGCCCCUGUCUUGUUCAUGUAGCCGAGGGGCAGGCGGGGGACCUCUACACCUCUGCUGUGGGCACGGGGCUGCUGAGGGUCUGUGGAACUCCAGCAGCUCUGCACUGGGUAGAGCUGGGCCUAGAGCUCAGUCACAGGCCUGGGCUUCCUGGCCUGAGUGGGUAGACGCAGGCGGCAGAGGUGCUGGACCACAUCUCCGCCAAGUCACUGCCCAGCAGCCUUCUCCGUCCUGUCCCCAGCCCACGUGCUCCUUGGGUGUCAGCUUCCUGUGCCUCUGUGGGAGAGGGCAGCUGCCUUGUGUUAUGUCUGGGGCCACAGUUGCUGCAAAGUCCUGGAUCUGCCACUCAACCCCGGGAGUGGUGUUCCCAGUGUGGCUCCCAGAGCUUUGACCAGAUUGUGAUCCCAGCUGGCCCCUAUGUUGUGUUCUGGACUGAGGCCUUUGCUGUGAACUGCAGUGUUUCAUACGAACCAUCUUUCCUAGUGCAUGAGAAAUAAAGAUUAUUUAAGUAA